GCAGAGCUCGGGCGCGGCGUCCUCCCUCCGCAGCAGCCGAGCCGGACCUGCCUCCCCGGGCGUGCUCCGCCGGCCCCGCCGCCGGCCCGCAGCGACAGACAGGCGCUCCCCGCAGCUCCGCACGGGACCCAGGCCGCCGGACCCCAGCGCCGGACCACCCUCUGUCCGCCCCGAGGAGUUUGCCGCCUGCCGGAGCACCUGCGCACAGAUGGAGCUGGACCACCGGACCAGCGGCGGGCUCCACGCCUACCCCGGGCCGCGGGGCGGGCAGGUGGCCAAGCCCAACGUGAUCCUGCAGAUCGGGAAGUGCCGGGCCGAGAUGCUGGAGCACGUGCGGCGGACGCACCGGCACCUGCUGGCCGAGGUGUCCAAGCAGGUGGAGCGCGAGCUGAAGGGGCUGCACCGGUCGGUCGGGAAGCUGGAGAGCAACCUGGACGGCUACGUGCCCACGAGCGACUCGCAGCGCUGGAAGAAGUCCAUCAAGGCCUGCCUGUGCCGCUGCCAGGAGACCAUCGCCAACCUGGAGCGCUGGGUCAAGCGCGAGAUGCACGUGUGGCGCGAGGUGUUCUACCGCCUGGAGCGCUGGGCCGACCGCCUGGAGUCCACGGGCGGCAAGUACCCGGUGGGCAGCGAGUCAGCCCGCCACACCGUUUCCGUGGGCGUGGGGGGUCCCGAGAGCUACUGCCACGAGGCAGACGGCUACGACUACACCGUCAGCCCCUACGCCAUCACCCCGCCCCCAGCCGCUGGCGAGCUGCCCGGGCAGGAGCCCGCCGAGGCCCAGCAGUACCAGCCGUGGGUCCCCGGCGAGGACGGGCAGCCCAGCCCCGGCGUGGACACGCAGAUCUUCGAGGACCCUCGAGAGUUCCUGAGCCACCUAGAGGAGUACUUGCGGCAGGUGGGCGGCUCUGAGGAGUACUGGCUGUCCCAGAUCCAGAAUCACAUGAACGGGCCGGCCAAGAAGUGGUGGGAGUUCAAGCAGGGCUCCGUGAAGAACUGGGUGGAGUUCAAGAAGGAGUUCCUGCAGUACAGCGAGGGCACGCUGUCCCGAGAGGCCAUCCAGCGCGAGCUGGACCUGCCGCAGAAGCAGGGCGAGCCGCUGGACCAGUUCCUGUGGCGCAAGCGGGACCUGUACCAGACGCUCUACGUGGACGCGGACGAGGAGGAGAUCAUCCAGUACGUGGUGGGCACCCUGCAGCCCAAGCUCAAGCGUUUCCUGCGCCACCCCCUGCCCAAGACCCUGGAGCAGCUCAUCCAGAGGGGCAUGGAGGUGCAGGAUGACCUGGAGCAGGCGGCCGAGCCGGCCGGCCCCCACCUCCCGGUGGAGGAUGAGGCGGAGACCCUCACGCCCGCCCCCAACAGCGAGUCCGUGGCCAGUGACCGGACCCAGCCCGAGUAGAGGGCAUCCCGGAGCCCCCAGCCUGCCCACUACAUCCAGCCUGUGGCUUUGCCCACCAGGACUUUUGAGCUGGGGCUGACUCCUGCAGGGGAAGCCCUGGUCCAGCUGGGUGCCCCCUCGAGCUCCGGGCGGACUCGCACACACUCGUGUCAUCCAGAUGUGAGCACCGCACCCAGCGGCAAAGAGCCCUCCCCCCUGCAGGGCUCCACCCAUCACCCUCCCUCCGUCUGUCUUUCCGGCCUGGACCCCACCCUCCACACUCUCAGGCCAUCACAGAACACCCCAGCUUCCUCAUUCUGCUACAACACCCAGGCCCUCUGGACAUCCAGAAAACCAAGUGUCCGGAUGGCAGGGGCCAGCGGCCACCAAGCUCAUGGGACACCCAGAGCAGAAGCUAGGGCAGAGCCAAUGCUGAGGGAGCCUCGACUUCCGGCGCCGCCGCCCUCUCCCGGCAUCCGCAGAGCCAGCUGACGCCCUCCCUGCCUCCCAGGGCAGCUGGCCAGCCUCGGGCAGCGCGGCCCCCUCCUCCCAGGGGAGAGUAGAAGUCGCACACGCAGCAGAGCAGACCUGAUGUCCCGGUGCUUCCUGGCCCCUCAGCUCCAGUGAUUCACGCCCGCCUGGAGAAGAAUCAGAGCUCAGCUCAUGACUCACCCAUGGCAGGCGGAGGGUCCCAGAGGGGCUGAGUCCUCAAAUCCGGCUGAGGCAGCAGCUGGCACCAUCAGAGCCAGGAGAGUGACAACAGGUAACGGAGCACCACCCUUCCACCCAGACCCCACCAUCAGCUGUCCCGGCCAAAUGAGCUCCUCCCCAGACCCCAGACACCCUGCGGCCCAGGCCACUCCCCAGUGUUCGGGCUCGCUGGGAGGCUCUGACGGGGUCGGGGGGCCUCUGCCUUGGAAGACCAGCGCCAUCCACCGGCCCCAGCCCCUCCCCAUGGAGCCCUGGCUACUGUCCUGCGUGGUCCUUCACUGCCCACUCUCCUGUUCUUUCAGGUCUCAAGGUUCCCACAAAGUCUUUGCUGCUGUGCUGGGCACCACCCACCCCUCACCUUGCAGGCUGCCUGCGUGGGAGGCGAAGUCCCAGGACAGCCCAGAGGGGGGCUACAGAGAGGAGUCGGCUGCAGCAGAGGGCAGGAGCCCCAGCUUAGCCCUGAGCGCCAGCGCGAGGACCAGGGCCUGCCACUAAGCCCGCCCCGCUGGCCGCCAGCUGCCCGUCCCCAGAGCCACUGCAGCAGGAGUCGGGCCCUGCCUCCCUCCCAGCAGGGAAACCCCGCCCGCUGCCAGGCCAUCCUCUCUGCCAGAGGCUUUCAUGAGCCCCAAGGCUGGGGCCACAGCUCCUACCCCUGCCCAGCAGCCCUGAGCUCAGCUGCAGGAAGGACAUCCCAGAAGCCAUGGCUCCUGGGGCGCUUCCAGGCAUUCUGCCCUGCCCCGACACCAGAACCCUGGUGCUGGUGGGCCACUAGCGUCUGCAGCCUAAGCAGGUGCUGGCUCAGGGUUCAUCGUUCUGCCUUGUCCACUGGGGGACCAGCCCUGCAGACCACUCUGACAAGUCUUCAGCCCACACCCUGCCAGCCCCACAGAUUUUAUUUUUGCACAUAAGCCAUAACCAAUCCUCAAGGCUGGCACAGGCUUUGGGGAAGCCCUGGAGCCUGUGAAGACCCUGGAAACCUCAUGAGGCUGUGGCCAACCCCUGCCCCUUGCCCCACACAGACCAGGCCUUAAAUGUCGGUCCAGGCCCUGUGCACCUUACCCCAGAGACAGACUCUUUUUGUAAGAUUUUGUUAAUAAAACACUGAAACUUC